CUUUAGAAACUACAGACACUUCUUCAGUCGAGACUAGAUACUAAAGAGAAAUUGUGUAGUUUUAUUGUAUCAGACUUAGUACAGGGGUGGGGUGGGGGUGUGUAUUGGAAUGAUGCGUGCCCGUUUCUCUGCAAAAUAGUUUCUAUGUCAUGGAAAGGAGUCGAUGGGACAAGAAGAGAAGUAUUUGAACAGUUGUGGGAGGAAACGACCUCUCCCACUGGCUGCGGAGAGUAUGCGGGUGUUGGUGUCAUCGUGGGUGCACUGCUUUCUGGCUGAACUGUCAAGUUCACUGUCUACACCCAAAAUUUUCACAUCCUUAACCGAAAAUUAUAGGUACCUCCAAGAGGCUGGCAAACGGCCUUAUCCAGUUCAAGUCCUGGUGUCAGAUUCACCUUGGAGCCAGAACUGAUUUGAAACCACAUCAUCCUGUGGUUGCGGAAGCCAGGUCUCCCCCGUAUAAUCCCAGAGUGCAUUUUGCAACAUCAGAGACCAGACCUGGAAAAGAUGUUUUAGUUUUUCUACCCCAACCUCCUUUUACUGAUGGGAAAACUGAGACCCAAAGGGGAGUGAGUUGCCCAGGGUCUCAGUGCGUUGGCAACAAGGCUAGGUAGGACCCAGACCUCCUUAACACCACCAGUCCAGUUAUCUUCUGUCAUAAUCACAGUGACUGUAUGUUCAGAAUGACUAUUGAUAUGUGUCCUACAUGAAGACAUUAGUACAGAAUAUGUAAGCUCAAGAUUUCCCUGACAAUCAAUACACCAGCUUGCUAAAUCAAUCCUGGGGACCUCCCUCUCCUGAGGCCACCACUGGGCCCCCUUCUGAGUGUCCCCUGAGCACUCUCUCAGCAUGAACUGCAUAUCCGACUUCUUCACCUAUGAGACCACCAAGUCGGUGGUUGUGAAGAGCUGGACCAUCGGGAUCAUCAACCGAGUAGUUCAGCUUCUGAUCAUCUCCUACUUUGUAGGGUGGGUUUUCUUGCACGAGAAGGCUUACCAGGUACGGGACACAGCCAUUGAGUCCUCGGUGGUAACCAAGGUGAAGGGCUCCGGACUCUACGCCAACAGAGUCAUGGAUGUGUCUGAUUACGUGACGCCACCUCAGGGCACCUCGGUCUUUGUCAUCAUCACCAAGAUGAUUGUUACUGAAAAUCAGAUGCAAGGAUUCUGCCCAGAGAGUGAGGAGAAAUACCGCUGUGUAUCAGACAGCCAGUGCGGGCCUGAGCGCUUGCCAGGUGGGGGGAUCCUCACUGGCCGCUGCGUGAACUACAGCUCUGUGCUCCGGACCUGUGAGAUCCAGGGCUGGUGCCCCACGGAGGUGGACACAGUGGAAACGCCCAUCAUGAUGGAAGCUGAGAACUUCACUAUUUUCAUCAAGAACAGCAUCCGUUUCCCCCUCUUCAACUUUGAGAAGGGAAACCUCCUUCCCAACCUGACAGCCAGGGACAUGAAGACCUGCCGCUUCCACCCGGACAAGGACCCUUUCUGCCCCAUCUUGCGGGUAGGGGACGUGGUCAAGUUUGCGGGGCAGGAUUUUGCCAAACUGGCGCGCACGGGGGGAGUUCUGGGCAUUAAGAUCGGCUGGGUGUGCGACUUGGACAAGGCCUGGGACCAGUGCAUCCCCAAAUACUCCUUCACCCGGCUCGACAGCGUUUCUGAGAAAAGCAGCGUGUCCCCAGGCUACAACUUCAGGUUUGCCAAGUACUACAAAAUGGAAAAUGGCAGUGAGUACCGCACCCUCCUGAAGGCUUUUGGCAUCCGCUUCGACGUGCUGGUAUACGGGAAUGCUGGCAAGUUCAACAUCAUCCCCACCAUCAUCAGCUCUGUGGCGGCCUUUACUUCUGUGGGAGUGGGAACUGUUCUCUGUGACAUCAUCCUGCUCAACUUCCUCAAGGGGGCCGACCAGUACAAAGCCAAGAAGUUUGAGGAGGUGAAUGAGACUACGCUGAAAAUCGCGGCUUUGACCAACCCAGUGUACCCCAGCGACCAGACCACAGCGGAGAAGCAGUCCACCGAUUCGGGGGCCUUCUCCAUAGGCCACUAGGGCCUCUUUCCAGGGCCCCACACUCACAAAGGCUCCAGGCCUCCCCACAGAGGACCCUGCCUGAGCAAGGGGCAUGGGAGGGAAGAGGGGCUCUCAUUUCUGCUGCUCAUUCCAUGAGCAUAGCUGGGACCCAAGUGUCUGGGCCUCCGACUGCUCCAGCAGACAGGCAGUGCUCCCUGCUGAGACCCCAAUCUCACCUUCACUCCUUGCCUGGCCCCAUCUGCUUCCUAGGACCCCUGGGGCAGGAGCACCUGAGCCAUCCCCUUCCCAAAGAGUAGAGAUUAUAAUGUAGGACAGAUGGCCACAAGGGCCUACCAAGUGCCAGGCACUUUCACACACGUUAUCUCAUUUAAUCCUUAGAAUAAUCCUAUGAGGUAGAUAUUAGUUUCCCUUGUUUUGAAGAUAAACCAAGGCUCAGAGAGACUGAGUCAUUUGCCCCAGGCCAGAUAGCCAGGAUGUGAGAGAGCUGGGAUUUGAACGUCCGUCUGACUAACUCCAUCGCCCACACCCCAUGAGAGAAGAAUGAACUCCCAGGGUCCAUCAGCCCUGCUGCUUCAGCCGCCUCCACCCUGACGGUGAUUCGGUUAAUAAAGAGUAAGCCCCAUGCCUUUCCCAGCAACAAAGUUUGCAUUUUAGGGAGACUGGUUAGACAGUGGUGAGGGACCCCAUCUCUGACUUGGGUGCAUCCCAAAUUUAGAAGGAAACAGAAGGCAUGGCUGUCAGUGAAUUUUUCCUCAUCACUCCCCAUAGCUCUCUCCCCAAACCAGGGAAGGGGUCAUUCUUGUUCUUCUCUGGGACCCCACACCCACACACAUCUGGGCCCCCUCACUCUGGGGAUUUGAUUCCCGGACCUGGGAUCCUGUCGUAGGCUGGGACCCUGUUCCAGGAGUUCAGCAGUCCUCAUUUACAACAACAGUGAAAAUGCUCCAGUAAGGCCUGGUGCCUUGUGAGCUGCUCAGCUGGGUUGGCCAGGCCUGUCCCCAUAGGGUCUUAAUAAGGUGCCCCAUUUUCUAAGGUUAGAAGCUAAAGGGGCCUUUUAAACCAUCUUAUCUAACCCUCUUGCUUACAGAUGAGCAAACUGAGGCCAGAAAGGGAAAAUGACUGGUUCAGUGCCACAGUUCAUGGCCAAAAAGGAACCCACAUGUCCUGGCCCUUCAGGGAAGGAGGCAAGAACAGGAAGCUGGAUCCAUUGACCCAGACAUCCUCUAUCCCCUUUCUGUCCUCUCCUACAGUGAGAGGCCCAGAAAUUGCCCCAGGGCAGGGCUCUGGGGCAGAACCAGGUUUUGUGAAUCCUAAGCAUAUACAAUUUGGGGGCAUCUCUUUAGAAAGAAUACAAAAUUAGGUAUUAGAAGGGGCUCAUGCAAGUGAAUGAGCCUAAAGAAUGUUUCAAUAGCUUCAUGAUAAAUCUGCAUCUGGCAGUCAGAGUGGGCAUGAUCAUGAGGUCUUAGCUGCACCAGCUCAACUGUAGAUGGAGGGCGGCCCCUCAACACACGGCACAGGAAGUGGGGAAGGGACAGCUUCAGGAGUAGUUCAGGAGGCUCAAAUGGUGGGUACUUGCAAAGGCCUUGCCCAAUGACCCCCCGCUCCAGGGGGAGAAGGGGUAAGACCCACCCCACAUAAAGCUCAACACCCCUUCCCUCACUCUGCCCUAACCCACAGCCCCAUGCCCAGGAUGGUGGGGCAUAUCUCCCCAGGGUCAGCCUUGGGAAUUGGGCAGUGCCUGGAGAUCUGACCAGACUAUGCUUCUCCAGCAGAGACAUCAGUGAAGGCAGCACCACAUUCUCCACCUGGGACUCCCCCAGGCAUCCCUGGGGAAUUCAGCUCUUGGGAGGCUGGGGUCACAGGGAUUCUCUCUAAUGGGGAGAUGGAGGCAGUGGUGUCCUGAAGGGACCCUCCCCCCCAACCCCUCCCUUUUACCCAGAUGGAGGUGGUCCUCCUGUAGGUGCCUCCGCCCCUCUGGAGCCGGCCAGCAAGUGUGUGUGAGCCUGAGGUUGUCCUCCGCAUAUCUGAACUAAGUUACCACUUCUGUGUGCUAGAUGUAGGGUUAAUAUCAGUAGUGAUAAAAACAGCUACCUUGUCUCUGUUGCAUUAUGGUUUACUCAGCACAAUCACCAACAUAAUCACAUGGACCCUCACACCAACGCUGGUGAGUCCGCUAUGGUUUGUCAUUAAUCCUAUUUGAUAGAAAAAGAAAUUUACAGUACGUGGAAAUGAGAUCUGGAACCUAUGCCCAUUCCUAACACUACAUUGCCUCUUUAAUCAUUCAACAUAAAAGCCAACACUGAUUACUUACUAUUGGCAGGCAAUGGACCAAAUGAGUGACAGGGAUUGUCUAACUCAACCCCCACUUUACAGAAGAAGAAACAGAUGCAUACUAAAAUAAAGAAACUGAAAUAGAA